AGCCCGCAGUGCAGGGGCAGCGCGGCGCGGGGCCACCGACGGGACGCGGCUCCGGGAACAUGGCUCGCUUCGCUCUGACUGUUGUCCGGCAUGGAGAAACAAGAUUUAACAAGGAGAAAAUAAUCCAAGGACAAGGAGUAGAUGAACCUCUUUCAGAAACUGGAUUUAAACAAGCAGCAGCUGCUGGUAUAUUUCUGAAUAAUGUGAAGUUUACUCAUGCUUUCUCCAGUGAUCUCAUGAGGACAAAGCAGACCAUGCAUGGAAUUUUGGAGAGAAGCAAAUUUUGCAAAGAUAUGACGGUAAAGUAUGACUCAAGACUUCGGGAAAGGAAAUACGGGGUUGUAGAAGGCAAAGCGCUAAGUGAGCUGAGGGCCAUGGCCAAAGCAGCCAGGGAAGAGUGCCCUGUGUUUACACCGCCCGGAGGAGAGACGCUGGACCAGGUGAAAAUGCGUGGAAUAGACUUUUUUGAAUUUCUUUGUCAACUAAUCCUGAAAGAAGCGGAUCAAAAAGAACAGUUUUCCCAAGGAUCUCCAAGCAACUGUCUGGAAACUUCUUUGGCAGAGAUAUUUCCUUUAGGAAAAAAUCACAGCUCUAAAGUUAAUUCAGACAGCGGUAUUCCAGGAUUAGCAGCCAGUGUCUUAGUUGUGAGUCACGGUGCUUACAUGAGAAGUCUGUUUGAUUAUUUUCUGACUGACCUUAAGUGUUCCUUACCAGCCACUCUGAGCAGAUCUGAACUUAUGUCAGUCACUCCCAAUACAGGGAUGAGUCUCUUUAUCAUAAACUUUGAGGAAGGAAGAGAAGUUAAACCAACGGUUCAGUGUAUUUGUAUGAACCUACAGGAUCAUCUAAAUGGACUGACUGAAACUCGCUAAGGUUAAAUCUGCAUCAAAAUCUAACCAUUUUGAGCCUCUGAAGGGAGUGCCAUUGGCUUUAUUUACUUCUCUCCUCUGCUAGUUCUGAUUUGGAAACAGUUAAAAGCCAAUUUUUAGCUCCAGUGGAACCAUAGCCACAUAAAACUUUAAUGGACAACCAUAUAGAAUUAACUUAUUUUGUCCAAGUACAGUUGGCAUUUUCCAGAAUAAUUUUACCACCCUGCUAGAUGUCAUCUCUGGAUUGCACAUGGAUGAUGAAGGAACUCAGCAUUGAAAGUUGGGGGAUUAGUAACCUUGUUACAACGGUUUCUUUUUCAUUUUAGCCUAUUUUAAUGGCUAUUGGUAAGAUACUGUAUGUUUUUAGUAUCUCAUCCAGUGCUUAGAAGAAAGAAUGGUUUAUAAUUCCCAGUACAUGUUUAUAUUGACUGUGUUAUAUUUUUAAAUCCUUUAAAUAAAAAAUCCUUAUAAGUUUAUGUAAAGCAAAAUAACACUAACAUGUUUUACGUAUAAAUCAACUAUUGGAAUUUUUUAUUCUAGAGGGCUUGAAAUGUGGAUGAAUACAGAUUAUGAUUGCAGAAUGGUCUGGGGGAAGAAGUUAAAACAUUUGAUUUAAAUACAGUAAAGAAAGAAUCUUGGAGCAGAAGAUAGAAGAACAGCCUUUUCUAAAUAAUGCCUUGCCAAAGUCAAGUCAAUGGAAACCAGGAAAGCCAAAAAAAUGAAGAAUAUCCACUUGCUUCUUAUCUAACCUGUAGGCUGAAGAAUUUCCAGUUUGAGGAAGGCUCUAAAGAAAGUAAACAGUUAACAGAACACCACACAGUAAUCAGAAUAAAAGAGGGGCCUUCUUUGUAAAGAAUGGUGCUCUGGGCCGGGCCCAGUGGCUCACACCUGUAAUCCCAGCACUUUGGGAGGCUGAGGCGGGCGGAUCACAAGGUCAGGAAUUCUAGACCAGCCUGGCCAACAAUGGUGAAACCCUGUCUCUACUACAAAUACAAAAAAGCCAGGCGUGGUAGCAGGCGCCUGUAAUCCCAGCUACUUGGGAGGUUGAGGCAGGAGAAUCGCUUGAACCCGGGAGGUGGAGGUUGCAGUGAGCCGAGAUCGCACCACUUCACUCCAGCCUAGGUGACAGAGGGGAUGACAGAGGGUGCUCUGCGGGCAGGGAAGGCGGGGUGGUUGGGGGGGAGAGAAUGUUGCUCUGAUAACCACAGCUGUGGUUAUUUUGUGGCAGGUACAGGUGAGGUUGCCUCUUCUUUCCACCAGAUGGCACUGGAGAAAAGGGAUUUUGAUUAACUUAAUUUUAUACACAAGAUUGGUCUUUCAGAAAUCUUUAUCUAAAUGAAGAAACUGUUCUACAUGUAGUUCGCUUUUAAGUCACCAUGUUGCUAAAUGCUGUGAGUCUCAACUUUAAAGAGGGUUAAUACUAAAGUUGUCAGUUAAGGCUAUAGUCACAUAUAGUCAAAAUUUACUUUGACAUCAUUUUAAAUCAUAUGUAAAAUUCAGUAUUAUAUUGUUCUUAGUGUGUCUAGCACUACCAGUUUUCUACCAGUAUUGAAACAGGGCACGUGUUUGAGCAUCAGAGGAAGUAUACUGUAAAUAAAAAUUUGAAAAAUAAGCAAAAAGGACAGACAAUAAUUAUCUCCAUUCCCACCAUACUGAAGUCAUCUUUCCACUUUUUUUUUUAAAGAAACAAAACAUAAAGAUAAAAGUAGAGUUCUCUUUAACCAGCUCUCACAGUCCUGUUCCCUCCAGAGGCAGCCACUGCAGUGAGUCUGUGUAUAUGUUCACCUGUUCAUCUGCUUGCAAUGUUCAUCUGUUCCUUAUAUUUUCACCUAGUGUCUGGAAGGAGAUGGUACUGUUUUGGUGCUUUAAAAAUAAAUAUCAAGCCAUCUGUGUUCUUUAUUUUUACUUAUGUCUUGGAGGCAUCUCUGUGUUGAUAUAUAUAGAUCUAGUUAAUUAUAACCACUCUAUUCUAUUAAAUAUAGCACAUUUUUGUUUAUUAGUGGGCAUUUAGGUAUAUUCAGUUUUUAUUUUCUUUGCUUUUUUUCUUUUUUUUUUUUUUUGGAGACAGAGUCUCUCUCUGUUGCCCAGGCUGGGGUGCAAUGGCGUGAUCUUGGCUCACUGCAACCUCCACCUCUCGGGUUCAAGCAAUUCUUGUGCCUCAGCCUCCUGAGUAGCUGGGACUACAGGCAUGCACCACCACGCCUGGCCUUUUUUUUUUUUUUAGUAGAGACGGGGUUUCGCCAUGUUGGCCAGGCUGGUCUUGAACUUCUGACCUCAGGUGAUCCACCUGCCUUGGCCUUCCAAAGUGCUGGGAUUGCAGGCAUAAGCCACCGUGCCUGGCCUAUGAUGCAUUUUUUUAAUAUGUGUUCUUAAUUUUUAAGACAAACCAAUAUACCUUAUCCUUUAUGGGGUUUUUUUGGUGUGUAUCUUUAAGAAGACUUCUCUACCAUGAGGUCAUACAGUAAUGUCUUCUUACAGUUUUUGAGAACUUCUGAAUGUCAAAUCUUGAAAUUGAAAUUUGCUUUUUAUAGUAUAAGGUAAGAAUUUAAUUUUUUUUUUCAUGUGGUUGAAACAGUUAUCCCAACACCAUUGUAAAGGCUGUUCUUUCCCAAUUGGUUUGUGGUGUGUGCUCUCAGGCCUCACACCCCCUCAUUUGCUAGAGUCUGUGGACUCUUUUAGUUAUCUGUGUAUUUCCUUAUCAGUGUCAUACUUAGUUACUGUGGCUUUGCAGCUGACUGUCUUAAAGGGUGGAUACCUCCUCUUGUUCAUUUUUAAAGUUGUCUUAACUAUUUAUGCACUUUUAUUCUUCCAUAUAAAUUUUGGAAUCAAUUGGUCAAUUUCCAGAAAAAUUCUGUUACAAAUUUUAUUGGAGUCACAUGCAUCUCUUCAUCUAUUCAAUACGUAUUUUUUGAGCAUGGCACACACAUGCCAGGCUAUUUUAAGAACUACUACAACUAUGAUAAAGCUGUGAAUAUGUAGCCAUGAACCAAAACAAAGUCUCUGUCCUUGUGGAACAUUUGUUCUGUCAGAGAAGACAGUGUGUUGGCUCACAUUGUGGUCAGUGCUGUUGAGCAAAAUAGGUCAGAGUAAGGGGGAUGGAGACUGGUGGGAGGAAUGCUGCUUUAUCCAGGAUGGGCAGGGAGGACUCGAUGGUGUCAGCACUGAAGGAUGUAAGAUCUGCUGCUCUGGGGAGAGGAGCAGCAUGGAAGGAGUAGAGUGCAGAGGCCAUGAGGAAGGAUCAGGCUUGACUCCUUUGAGCAAGGGGGAUGGGAGAGUGACGGGAGAAGAGGACAGGCCACAUGGCCUGGUGGCCUGUGCUGAGGCCUUGGGCUUUUACUCAAGUGAGAUGAGAUGCCAUUGGCCAGUUUGGGCAGUGAUGUGAUCAGACUUGUUUCAGCAGGACCAUCCUGCUUGCAAUGUGGAGAGCAGGCUGUAGGGGGUGCUAUAGGAGCACAAGGUUGGAGGCAGGGAAGAUGGCAGCACUGGCUGUUGGGCCAUUUGAAGAAGCAAGGCCAGGGAUGUUGGCAGGGACCAGGCCAGAGUGCCUCCAAUGGCUAACUAAGGAGCCUGGACAUUGAAUUUCUAGGUUAGCUUAGGAUUUCUCAUCCUCCCAUCUGUGAAUGUCAUAGAUCUCUCAUUUUGCCUGAGUCUUUUAUGCAAUGAUAUUUUAUUUGUAAUAUUUUCCCGGUUUUUGAUUGUUUUUUAACAAAUGAAUUUUUUAAGAGACUUAAUUUUUUAAGAGAAACUUUAAUUUCCCAGCAAAAGUGAGAGGAAGGUAGAGAGAUUUCCCAUCUAUCCCCUGCCCCUACACACGCAUUGCUUCUCCUACUAUCAACAUCCCCCACCAGACCAGUGCAUCUGUUACCAUCGGUGAGCCCACAUUACACUGACAUAUCCACAUCACCUGAAACCCAUAGUUUACAUUAGGGUUCAUUCUUGGUGUUGCAUGAUCUGUGGGUUUGGACAAACGUAUGAAGACAUGUAUUCCACCAUUAUAGUAUCAUGCAGAGUAUUUUCACUGCCCUAAAAGUCCUCUGUGUUCCCUGUACUCAUCUUUCCCACCUUGUCUUGCCUGUUUCUGUUAGGUUUAGUCCGAGGCCUAGCAGAGGGAAUGGGCAGAAGUUUCCAGUUCCAGGCUUCACCCCAGGCUCGCAGCUUCAAGCAGAGCCUGUCGCUUAGGCUCCCUUGCACCUGGAGUCGAAACCAUGGCUCCCAUUCACCUGUCUCUUAUUUUCCUGUCCUUCCCACUCCUCACUCACCUACUAUUCAUUUCCAUUUUUGGAUGAGGAUUCUCCUUUAUUGCUUUUUAACUAAAAACCUGUUUUAGUUAGCAUCUUUAUUCUAAUUUCUUUAAAUGCUAUGUCAUACUCAGCAAGGACAUGCUCAUAUUAGGGGAAGCACAUAAAGUAAGAUAUCCCUGAGAGAACAGUGCAUCUCACACCCAUUCCAUGGCUUAGGCUUAUGCAGGAAGUGCAAUAUUUGGCCAUAUCACUUAAGUACAUAUGCUUAUAUUAUGUAUACUUGCAUGCAUAUUACAUUUACAAGUAGAUGAAUUCGUGUAAGUUAAAUGGUUCUAUUAUAUGUCUUCACUAUAUUAAGGUCAGUCACAAUUUAAUUGAAAUAGAUCAUCCUAGGUGAAUCCACCUGGCAUAAUUAUCAGCCCUGUUAAGCACAGACACAGGAGAUGCAAAGGAAAGAAGUAUUCAGUAGAGCGGUGGUGCUGGGCUGAGUACCUGCUAUCAGACGCAGCACUUACCAGUUUGGAAAUUGAAUGGGGCUCCUAGAAAACAUCCUUGUUUCAUGUAAAUGUUGCUUUUUACCCCUCUUUCUUUGGGCCCCAUCAAUUUGGAAGUACAGCUUUCAGAUUGAAGUAUGUGUCAGUUCCUUUGUGUCCAAACAAGAUGGCUAAGUAGGUCGUCAUGACAGGUAACUACCAGUGCUUUAAAAACUUUAGGAUUUCCCCCCACAGUUCUCAAUCACUUGGUUCAUUGUUCAGCAAUAUGGCCUAAGGGGGUGAUUUCUUCAUUGAUAAGUGACAGGGCAGGGACACUGGAAAGAUCUAUUGUCAGAAGGCCUGGAUUCAGGUUCAAGGCCUGGUUCUUAGUAAUUUUGUGACCAAGCAAUCGCUGAGGUGGCUGGGCGUGGUGGCUCGCACCUGUAAUCCCAGCACUUUGGGAGGCCAAGGCGGGCAGAUCACGAGGUCAGGAGAUAGAGACCAUCCUGGCUAACACAGUGAAACCUCGUCUCCACUGAAAAAUAGAAAAAAUUAGCCAGGCCUGGUGGCCGGCGCCUGUAGUCCCAGCUACUUGGGAGGCUGAGGCAGUAGAAUGGCGUGAACCCGGGAGGUGGAGCUUGCAGUGAGCCAAGGUCGCGCCACUGCACUGCAGCCUGGGUGACAGAGCAAGACUGGGUCUCAAAAAAAAAAAAAAAAAAUCAUUUGAUAAAUAAUGGGCUGUGCAUGGUGACUCAGGCCUGUAAUCCCAGCACUUUGGGAGGCCAAGGUGGGUGGAUUACCUGAGGUCAGGAGUUCAAGACCAGCCUGGCCAACAUGGUGAAACCCUGUCUUUACUAAAAAUACAAAAAUUAGCUGGGCGUCUCCAAAAAAAAAAAAAAAGAAAAAGAAAAAUCACUGAGCUACUGUAUCCUCAUAGAGAAUAAUUACAGUAAUGUGUAUGUGCGUGUGUUUUGGUAAUCUUUUAUCUUGGAUUUAUCAAACCUACAGAAAAGUUGCAAGAACAGUAGAAGGAAUGGCUGUAUACUCUUCACACUUAUUCACCACUUGCUUACCUGUUGUCCCACUUGCUUUGCCAUUUUUUCUCUCUCCCUCUGUUUUCCCCUGAAACAUUGGAGAGUAACUUUGAGUCCUCAUACUCUUCCCCUAUAAAAUUUCAAUGUGUGUUUCCUGAGAUCAACAAUGUUCUUAUAUAUAACCCAGAAUAAAUAUCUGAGUCAGGAAAUUUGACAUUGAUAUUGCCUAUUAGCUAAUCCUUAGACCAAAUUUAAAUUCUGUCAAUUAUUUUGUUGAUGUACCUGUGGCUUUUUUUUUUUUUCUGAAUCAAGAAUCCAAUCAAUCCAGGACUGUGUGUUGUGUUGCAUUUAGUUGUCAUGUUUCUUCAUGUCCUUCCGUCUACUCCUUUGCCUUCCUUUGCCCUUCUUUUUUUCUCCCACCAUCUAUCUAACCAGAUGAACUUUGUCUUUCUUGAUCUUGUUACUUUUUAAAAAAUAGGUGAGUUCUUGUGGUUUUUUUUCCUGACAUAUCCUCAUUAUUAGAUUUGGAUUGUAUACUUUUGUCAGAAGCAGCCCAGAAAGGAUGUGUCCUUGGUCAUGUCAGGAGGGACAGGACGUUGUAUCAAUAUGUCUGGUUCCUCAUUAAAUUUGCAACUACUCUUUUAGCCUUUAUUGUUUAUUUUCUGACUCUGUUUUUUUUUUCUUUAGCCAACUCACGCCAUGACUCUACUUUUGCUUCUAUGUUUAUUAGUUGGCAUUCUGUACUAAGACAGCUUUACCCUUCUUGCCUACUUAUUUAUGUCAGUAUGAGCUCAGAAGUUCUUAUUCAGGGGCUUAUAAUACAGUACUCUUAUUAUUUUAUGGUUACACAGUCCCAACUUUGUCCUGUGGGAACCCUUUCAGGCUGGCUCUUAUGUUCUGGUGACAUAAUCUCAUCCUUCUUUAAGUACUUUCUUUCUGGUAUUAACAAUAUGCUCCAGACUCAUUCUUCCCGAGCCCCAGCCCCAGAAUCAGCUUUUUCUCUAAAGAGCCCUGGUUCUUUGGAAAUGAAAUGAAAGACGCCUGGUGUGCAUGGUAUUUAGAAACCAAGAUCUCGGUGCCAGGGUGCUCAUUGCUAAUAGUGCCUUUAAAAAAAUUACUGCAUUGAAUUCCAAUGCAUAGAUACACAACAGUUUGUUUAUUCUUCCAUUGACGGAACACAAGGACCAUUUCUAGUUUGGAGCUAUUAUGAAUAAAGCUGCUAUAAAUAUUUUUACAAGUCUUUUUGCGGACGUAUGUUUUCAUUUCUCUUGGGUAAAUAAUCUGGGAGUGGAAUUGCUGAGUUAUAGGUUAUAUGUUGGUGUAUGUUUAGUUUUAUAAGACACUUGCCAGAUCUUUUUCCAUGGUGGUUGUACCAUUUCAUGCUUAUCAACAAUGAGUUCUAGGUGCUUCACAUCCUUGCCAACAUUUGUUAUUAUCAGUUUCUAAAAUUUUAGCCAUUCUGAUUGUUGUAUGGUAGUAUAUCCCUGCAAUUUUAACUGGUGAUAUGGAAUGCUUUUUAAUGUACAAUUCUUAUUGAUCAUUCAUACAGCUUUCUUUGUGAAAUGUGUAUUAAAAUCUUAUCCAUUAAAAAA